GGCCAGAGGCACCGGCUAGAGCUGGGAGCUUGCGGAAGGGCGCCCCUGCCUGGUCUUGAGAGGUCGAAGGUCUCCAGGAGGCCUCCGCCUCCCUCUUUUUCAUUCACACACCCUAGCCUCACACGUUAGGAGGACCCCCCCAACAGACCGUGAGCUGGUGCCGGGAGGGUGGAGGUAGAUGUACCUCACCUCCACGCUACCACAGAAGAGCGAAAGCUGCUUUCUCAGCCACCGGAGAGCACGAAGAAGAACUAUAUAUUAUAAAGCAUUCAAAGGCAAGUGAGAAUUCAAAUCUGUAGAACAGAACUAGAGAGCUUUUACAGAGAGGCCUUUGGGAGAAGAAGAUAUACUGGCAAGUUCUAGAAGGAUUCUACCAUUUUCUUCUUUACCAUGAACAAACUUGAAAAUUAAUGGGUAAUAGUUGCAUGAAAACUUUUGAACGUUUUUUCUUAUCUCUGAGGCCUUCUAUGGAGAAUUAAUAGGAGGUUGAAUGUGUGCAUGGAUAAAAUGGAUCAUCUUAAAGGAUUGAAGUUCCAAAAAUACAUCAGCAGGACUGGACAGGUUUUAUAUAAUGAGAUUUCUAUUUUAGCUUGACUUCUACAACUCUGAAUAAGCUAUAAACUGAGCUAUACAAGGUACUAGGAAGGAAGUUUCUCUUCUAAAAUAUUCUAGUUGCAUAUAAUAUUUUUCUUCAGAUCUUUGAAAAAGCAUAUUUUGUCAUCAAGUUCCUACAAAAUAAGACUAUUAGACACCAACUUUUAGUGUAUAAAGUAGGAUAGAAAGCAGCAAUCUAUAUUAUACUGGAAAACAAAUUUAAUUAAAGAAACAGUCACCAGGAAGUUAAGAAGAGUAAUCUCUACAUAAGCACUGGCUGAGAUGGCAGAAGCUUCUGUGGAUGCCUCAACUCUGCCUGUAACAGUGAAGAAAAAGAAAAGCCUAUCCAUUGAGGAAAAGAUCGACAUCAUAAAUGCAGUGGAAAGUGGCAAGAAAAAAGCAGAGAUUGCUGCUGAAUAUGGAAUAAAGAAAAAUUCAUUGUCUUCUAUUAUGAAGAAUAAAGACAAAGUUCUAGAAGCCUUUGAAUCUCUAAGAUUUGAUCCAAAGAGAAAAAGACUGAGAACUGCUUUUUACACAGAUCUGGAAGAGGCAUUAAUGAGAUGGUAUCGAAUUGCUCAGUGUCUAAAUGUACCAGUUAAUGGUCCGAUGUUACGUCUAAAAGCUAAUGAUUUUGCCCAGAAACUGGGCCAUAAUGAUUUUAAGUGCAGUAAUGGUUGGCUGGAUCGUUUUAAAUCCAGGUAUGGUUUAGUAUUCAGAGCUCAACCUGUAGAAGCUACAGGUGUACCAGUAGACCCUUCGACUGUCUGGUACCAAAAUGUACUUCCUUAUUAUUUAAAUGAUUAUCAUCCUAAAAAUGUUUUUAAUAUAAAAGAGACUGGGCUGCUUUAUCGAAUGUUACCUACCAAUACAUUUGCAUUUAAAGGCGAAACAUGUUCAGUUGGAAAGUUAUGCAAAGACAGAAUAACUCUGGUGGUUGGCACAAACAUGGAUGGCUCAGAGAAACUUCCUUUGCUUGUCAUUGGAAAAAAGAGAACUCCACAUUGUUUCAAAGGUUUAAAAUCAUUGCCUGUGUGUUAUGAAGCUAACAGAAUGGCAUGGAUGACCUCCGAUGUAUUUGAACAAUGGAUGCGAAAGCUUGAUGAGGAAUUUCAAGCCCAGCAACGAAGAGUGGUGAUUUUUGUUGAGUCUUUUCCAGCACAUCCAGAGGUAAAGAACCUAAAAUCCAUUGAGUUAGCAUUCUUUCCAUCAUGUUUAUCUUCCAAAUGUAUAGCUAUGAAACAAGGUGUUAUUAAAAGCCUUAAAAUCAAAUAUCGACACUGUCUUAUCAAGAAAUUUUUAAGCUCUGUUGAAGGUAGCAAAGAAUUUACAUUUUCACUACUAGAUGCAGUUGAUACAUUGCAUCUUUGCUGGAGGGCUGUAACCCCAGAGACUAUUGUUAAAAGCUAUGAAGAGGCAGGAUUCAAAUCUCAAAAGGGAGAAAGUGACAUAACAAAUGCAGAGAAGGAUACUGGUCUGGAUUUGGUUGCUGAUGCUCUGGGGGCAGGAGUAGAAUUUCCUGAAGGUUUAUCUAUAGAAGAAUAUGCUGCCCUGGAUGAUGAUUUGGAGACAUGUGAAGCAGCACCAAAUGGUGAUUCCAUAUGCACCAAAGAAAGUAAAUCGGAUGAAACUGGAUUUUACACUUCUGAUGAAGAGGAUGAUGAUGGAUCUCCAGGAACUGAACUCCCUUUACCAUCAAAAUCUGAGGCAAUAACUGCUUUAGAUACUCUGAAAAAAUUUCUCAGAAGUCAAGAUAUGAAUGACGGACUUCAAAAUUCUUUAGCAGACCUUGAAAAUUUUAUUAACUCUUUAUCACCUAAGUAACUAUGUAUUGUACAUCUAAAGAGUAAUAGCUUUUCCUGAUACAUUUUAUUAUAUAAGGUAUGUAAAGGAGUUGUACCACACCACUUAAACAUAAAAAAUGGAAAACUGCUAA